CUUUCCUGGCGGCAGACACACAUCGCAAGGAUAUUUACAGAGCGGACAGCUGGAAUAGCUGUAGGAACGUCAAGACUAAUCCCGGUAUGCGGAAGUAGAUCAAUAUUUGCACAUCGUGAUCUAGCUGGAUCUGCAAUAUAGACAGGUAAAGGUUGACAUUAGGAGUGCAUAGGUCCUGAGCAUCUACACGCGGUGCCACUGGGUCGCCAGAAGAACAGCGCACUUCAGGGGCACAGAGUGGGGUUGAAGGGUCUGCACACCAGCGCUUGCAGUGUGAGCAGCAAGAGAUCCAGCUCACAGAACCAAACCUGCUGCGAUCCAUGUGACACUGGCAUACUCCAGAAUUGUCCAUUGGAAACACGAGUUCAAGUGCCUCAGGGAGAUUCAGGAGGAGGAACACAGCCCACCCACACUGCACCCCCUUUGCAGUCUGAAGGCAAGGGAUGCUCUGAAGAGCAGCUUGGUUUAGGAGAGACCUACGGUAGCAGAGGGUGUGGCAGGCAGACCCCUCGGCCUCCCUUAGCUACCUUUUCCCAGCUCAUCAUGGACUCGGAGUACGUCCUAUGCUCUUGGAAAGGCCGACUAUGGCCAGCAAAGGUUUUGUGCACACGUGGGACUUCACCAAAAACGAAGCCUGAAAAGGCGAUUUCUCUAGAAGUUCAAAUCCUCGCAGUAGAUGAAAAAAUCAAGGUGAAAAGCACAGACGUGAAGACCCCAACUAAGUUUGAGAUGGAAGACAUUGCCGCCUCUGCAGCAGCACAGACGAAGCUCGGUGCCCCACUCAGAGAGAAGAUGGGGUACAGAGGAACCCUUCGGGUGGCCCUGGAGAUUCUGAAAGAGAGAACAAAUCUGGGUGGAGGAAGGAAACCACAUGAACUAGAGAGCACCACACCCUCUCAGCUUUCUCAAAAGGUGCCCGAAAAGCCAGCCAGUUCUGUCCCUCGUGAAGAUGACUGGAGAUGCAAAGGCGACCUAAGGAGGAGUCUUGGGAAGAGGGAAAACCCAAGCUCACCGACGGUCCCUUCAGAGAGUAAGCGUGCCCUGCGGGAUGACAGGUCGCAGGAGCCCACAGCCAUUGCCCCUACUCCAGGCGCCCUGCCCGGGGACAGGUCAGGGGCGCCCAGGGCCAUUGCCCCUACUCCAGGAGCCAUGCUCAGUGGCAGGUCACGGGCACGCAGGGCCAUUGCCCCUACGCCAAGCGCCCUGCGAGGUUACAGGUCUUGGGCGCACAGGGCCAUUGCCCCUACCCCAGGCUGCCUGUACAGUGACAGGUCACGGGCGCACAGGGCCAUUGCCCCUGCUCGAGGCACCAAGCAUGGUGGCAGGUCAUGGGCAUGCAGGUCCAUUGCCCCCAAACCAGGCUCCCUGUGCGGGGACAGGUCACAGGCGAGCAGGGCCAUUGACCCUACCUUAGGCGCCAGGCGCGGUGGCAGGUCACGGGCCCACAGAGCCAUUGCCCCUACUCCAGGCUCCCUGUGCGGCAACAGGUCACGGGCUUGCGGAGCCAUUGCCCUUACUCCAGGUGUCCUGUGCGGUGUCAGGUCACGGGUGCCAAAGGACAUUACCCCUACUCCAGGCGCCCUGCGAGGUUACAAGUCAUGGGUGUGCAGGGCCAUUGCCCCUACUCCAGGUGCCCUGCGCGGAGACAGGUCAGCAGCACGCACGGCCGUUGUCCGUACUCCAGGUGCCCUUGGCAGGGACAGGUCACGGGCACGCAGCGCCAUUGCUUCUACUCCAGGGACCCUGCAGGGAAACAGGUCAUCUGUGUCCAAGGCCAUUGCCCCUACUCCAGGUGCCCUGCGUGGAGACAGGUCAGCAGCGCGCACGGCCUUUGUCCCUACUCCAGGCGCCCUUCACAGGGACAGGUCACGGGCCCGCAGCGCCAUUGCUUCUACUCCAGGGACCCUGCGGGGAAACACGUCAUCUGCGUGCAAGGCCAUUGCCCCUACUCCAGGUGCCCUGCGAGGUUACAAGUCAUGGGCGCGCAGGGCCAUUGCACCUAACCCAGGUGCCUGGCGCGGUUACAGGUCAACGACAGGCACCGCCAUUGCACCUAAUCUGGGCGCCCUGGGCGGCAACAGGUCAGCGGCACGCACGGACAUUGCCCCUACUCCAGGCGCCCUGCGAGGUUACAGGUCAUGGACGCGCAGGGCCAUUGCCCCUACUCCAGGCACUCUGAGCAGUUACAGGUCACGGUCCCGCAGGACCAUUGCCUCUACUCCAGCCACCCUGCGUGGUGAAAAGUCACGGGCGCACACCAGCCUUGCCCCCACCCCAGGUGCUUUGCGCGGUGACGGUUCACGAGCACGCAGGGCCAUUGUCCCUACUACAUGCCCAUUGUGCGAGAUAUGGUCACGGGUGGGCAUAGGCAUUGCCCCUAUUGCAGAUGCCCUGCGCCGUGACAGGUCACCAGUGCGCAGGGCCAUUGCCCCUACUCCAGGCACUCUGAGCGGUUACAGGUCACGGGCACGCACGGCCAUUGCCCCUACUCCAGGCACCCUGCGAGGUUACAGGCCACGGUCCCGCAGGGCCAUUGCCUCUACUCCAGCCACCCUGCGUGGUGAAAAGUCACGGGCGCACACCAGCCUUGCCCCCGCCCCAGGUGCUUUGCGCGGUGACGGUUCACGAGCACGCAGGGCCAUUGUCCCUACUACAUGCCCAUUGUGCGAGAUAUGGUCACGGGUGGGCAUAGGCAUUGCCCCUAUUGCAGAUGCCCUGCGCCGUGACAGGCCACCAGUGCGCAGGGCCAUUGCUCCUACUCCAGGCGCCCUGCGCUGUGACAGGUCACGAGAGCUCACAGCCAUUGAUCCUACUCCAGGAGCUCUGUGCAGUGACAGGUCAGGGGCAAGCAGGGCCAUUGCCCCCACUCCAGGCACUUUGUGCAGUGAAAGGUCCCGGGUGCGCAGGGCCAUUGCCCCUACUCCAUGCGCACUGUGCGGGAAGGGGUCACAGGUGGGCAUGGGCGUUGCCCCUACUCCAGGUGCACUGCGCAGGGACAGGUCACAGGCAGGCAGGGCCAUUGCACCUACUCCAUCCGCACUGUUCAGGGUUGGGUCACGGGUGGGCACAGGCAUUGCCCUUCCUGCAGGUGCCCUGCACCGUGACAGGUCACCGGUGCGCAGGGCCGUUGCUCCCACUCCAGGCACCCUGCACUGUGACGGGUCACGAAAAUGCACGGCCACUGGUUCUACUCCAGGAGCCCUGCCCGGCGACAGGUCAGGGGUGAGCAAGGCCACUGCCCCUGCUCCAGGCGCCUUGUGCAGUGAAAGGUCCCGCGCACGCAGGAGCAUUGCCCCUACUCCAUGUUUACUGUGCGGGGACAGGUCAUGGGUGGGUAUGGGCAUUGCACCUACUCCAGGCGCCCUGCUUGGUGGCAAAUCAAGGAAAUGCAGGGCCAUUGCUAUUACUCCCGGCGCCCUGCGUGGUGGCAGGUCACAGAAACGCAGGGUCGUUGCUCCUACUCCAGAGGCCCUGCACGGUGACGGGUCAUGGACUUAUAUGGCCAUUGCUCCUACUCCAGGUGCCCUGCACGGUGACAGCUCACCAGCCCACACGUCCAUUAUUCCCUCUCCAGGCGCCCUGCAUGGUGACGGGCCACCAGCGCACAUGGCCUUUCCUUCUACUCCAGGCACCCUGCAUGGUGAUGCCUCUCACGCACACAUGGCCAUUGCUCCUACUCCAGGCACGAUGCGCGGUGACAGCUCAACAGCGCGCACGGCCACUGCCCCAUCUCCAGGGGCCCUGCGAGGUGACAGGUCAUGGAAACGCAAGGCCAUUGCUUCUACUCCAGGUGCCCUGCAUGGUAACAGGUCUGACAGGUCACGGAAAUGCAAGGCCAUUGCUUCUACUCCAGGCACCCUGCACGUUGAGAGGUCACCAGCACUCAGGGCCAUUGUUCCAACUCCAGGCACCCUGGGCCGUGACAGCUCACCAGGGCGCACGUCCAUUAUUCCUUCUCCAGGCGCCCUGCAUGGUGACAGGUCACCAGCACACCUGGACAUUGCUUCUACUCCAGGCGCCCUGCACGGUGACAGCUCUCAGGCACACACGGCCAUUGCUCCUACUCCAGGCACCAUGCGCGGUGACAGCUCAACAGCUCGCAUGGCCAUUGCCCCAUCUGCAGGGGCCCUGAGAGGUGACAGGUCAUGGAAACGCAAGGCCAUUGCUUCUACUCCAGGUGCCCUGCGUGGUAACAGGUCUGACAGGUCACGGAAACGCAAAGCCAUUGCUUCUACUCCAGGUGCCCUGCUCGGUAACAGGUCUGACAGGUCACGGAAACACAAGGCCAUUGCUCCUACUCCAGGUGCCCCGCGCAUUGACAGGUCACCAGCAUGCAGGGCCAUUGCUCCUACUCCAGGCGCCCUGGGUGAUGACAGCUCAACGGCCAUUGCCCCUACUCCAGGGACCCCGCGAGGUGACAGUUCGCCAGCAAACACGGCCAUUGCUUCUACUCCAGGCGCCCUGCACGGUGACACCUCUCAGACACACAAGGCCAUUGCUCCUACUCCAGGUGACCUGGGCGGUGGCAGCUCAUCAGCGCACAAGGCCAUCACUCCUUCUCCAGGUGCCCUGCAUGGUGACAGGUCACCAGCACACACGGCCAUUGCUUCUACUCCAGGAGCCCUGCAUGGUGACAGCUCCCAGGUGCACACGACCAUUGCUCCAACUCCAGGCGCCCUGCGCGAUGACAAGUCAUGGAAACGCAAGGCCAUUGCUCCCACUCCAGGCACCCUGCACUGUGACAGCUCACGAACGUGCACCGCCUUUGCUCCUACUCCAGGCGCCCUGCAUGCUGACAGGUCACCAGCGCACCAGGACAUUACUCUUACUUCAGGCGCCCUGCACUGUGACAGCUCAAGAGAAAGCAGGGCCGUUGCUCCUAUUCUAGGCGCCCUGCACCGUGUCGGCUCUCAGGCACACAAGGCUAUUGCUUCUACUCCAGGCCCUCUGCGCGGUGACAGCUCACCAUUUCACACAGCCAUUGCACCUAUGCCAGGGGCCCUGCAUGGUACCAGGUCAUGGAAACGCGAAGCCAUUUCUCAGACUCCAUUUGUCACCCUGUGUGGUGACAGCUCAGGAGAACGCAUGGCCAUUGCUCCUACUCCAGGCGCCCUGCACAGUGACAGGUCACAGACACAUACGGCCAUCGAUCCUACUCCAAGUGUCCUGCGCAGUGACAGCUCACCAGCGUGCAUGGCCAUUGAUCCUACUCCAGGUGCCCUGGGCAGGGACAGGUCACAGGCGCUCAUGGCCAUUGCUCCUACUCCAGUUGGAAUGCAAGCACAUGUGUUGCAAAGCCCCCGAGCCUGCCAGGAUUCCCUGACGCUUUCGCGGCAUGUUUGUGAGAAAAAGGGGAAGAAAAGGGCAAACGCCUCGACUCUUAUGUCCCUGCCUCCCACAGUAACGGAGGAGGGUGCAUCUCUGCCUCCAGGUCUCACCAGCCCUGCACCCCCCGCUCUGAAGGAAGAGACACAGGACAGCCGCCCGAAGAAGGCCCUGGCUGCAUCCCCGGAAAGUUCUCCCUUCUCGGGAAACAUUCAGGACCCCGGAGAGGGUGCCUGGAAGCCAGGCUGGGCAGGUAUGGCUGCAUCCUCUGGGUCCCGUCAGCACAGGCUGCCUUCUUCACUCCGGCUUGCCAAUAGAAAAAGGAAGCGUCCAGGUCCAGAUUUUCAGAGGAGACCUCAAGGACCUCAGACGCCUGGUGACGCUAAGCUUGCUAAUCCUGUCACCACCAUUCAAAGGGCUGGCGGUAAACAGGAUGGGCAGCCCCCCAGCCUUGCUUUUCCACAGGAGCCACAUCCCAUCGAAAGGGGAACGAUGGUCUGGUUCAAAUUUCAAGAUCAUCCGUUUUGGCCAGCAGUGGUCAAGAGUGUCAGCAACACAGACAAGACCGCGAGGGUGCUCCUGCUUGAGGCCAACCUGCACCAUGGAAAGCGGGGCAUUCAAGUUCCUCUUCGAAGGCUGAAGCACCUGGAUUGUAAGGAGAAAGAGAAACUGCUGAAGAGAGCCCAGAAGGCCUACAAGCAAAGCGUCAACUGGUGCUUCUCACUGAUCUCCCACUACAGAGAAGGACUGGUCCGGGGUUCUUUCCGGGGCUCUUUCCUGGACUAUUAUGCCGCAGACAUCAGCUACCCAAUCAGGAGAGCCAUCCAAGAGGGAGACCUGCAGAUUGACUUUCCAAAGGUGAAUUAUGGCGACCUGGAAGACUGGGAGGAGGAGACCUCCCUGGGCGGGAAGAGGCCUUGCAAGAAAAUCCUCCCGGACCGGAUGAGGGCCUCUUGGGACCGAGACAACCAGAAGCUCGUGGACUUCAUCGUGAGGAGAAAGGGGGCCGACCCCCACCUUCUGGACAUCUUGCAAGGCAGGAAGCAGUCCAGGUGGCUGACCGCGUUUCUGAAGCCACACAGGGAUUUGCACUGCAUUGAAACAUACCUGGAGGAUGACGAUCAGUUGGAAGUCGUGGCCAAGCAUUUACAAGAAAUCUACAAGCAAAUUGACAAGGCCAGGCUGACUCUGAUAAGGGAUGACAAAGUCAAUUUUGUUCUGGAAGUUCUUCUGCCGGAAGCCAUGAUUUGUACCAUCGCCGCACUUGAUGGGCUGGAUUACAAGGCAGCAGAGGAGAAGUACCUGCGAGGACCACCUGUGCAUUACCGGGAGAAAGAGCUGUUUGACAGAAAUAUCUUAAAGAAGGCAAGAAGAGAACCAGCAACCACCCAUACAGCUAAUUAGCUCCCGCCUGCCUCCCCCGCACCCAUACCUUCCCAGGGAGCUGCCUCCUUUCUAGAAUUAAUGAGGAAGCCUCCUCCCUUCCCCAACGCGUGUAAGUAUGUUCUGGAUAUUCGAGACUUUGGGAAUGUGAGGAAUUCAUUUGGGGCCCAUCUCUCGCAUGUGCUGGUGGCACAUUCAUCACCAGGUCUUCAUCGCAAACUCGUGAAGAGCUAUUUUGUUAAACGAUUGCAACCCCUUGCGAUUCCCUCAACGUCUUUGGAUGUGUAGUUGUCCCGAUAGGUUUGAAAGACAAGAGCAUUGAUUUUCAUAACGUGUCUUUUGACUGGACUUGGUACUUUCACUUAGGACCUAUAUUCUUUUACACAAAAAGCCACUGGUAUCAGCUUUUAAACAACAAUAAUUUUUAAAGCCUAAUGUAUAUUUUUAUGGAAACGUCAGUGAGACUUUUCAUUCUUUUGGCGAUACGUGGAUAGAAACCAUCAGAUUCCUCUUUCAGAUAAUUCCUGCCUUUUCCCUGCUAGGCUUGUUUAUUUUUUGAAAAGUAGCCCCGAGAGUUGAAUCCCAUGAGAGAGUCAUUUUCUCCUAUGUUAACACGACCUUCCGAUACUUUUUCAAAAAGCAAACUGCAGGCCAAACAUGAAGUUACCGAAUGGCUUGCACGUAGUCCAUAUGUGCUUGAGUGAAAUCUCAGUGUGCAGUGAGCGUCUUGUCAGCCUCAUGCAAGAUUGUCGCUCUGCAUUUCCCUGAAAUUCCACACCCUCCUUCAACGGCUGAACUGUUUCCUAGAACAGGCUUCAGGCUGUCUUCAUAACUGACAGUGAUGGAUCUUCUCCCUCUAACUGUCGGUCCCCUGUGGAGGGCAGCUAGAGCCAUCUCCUUCUUGGCCUGGCUUCUCUCCACCUGUGUGGCUGGCCCAACUGCUUAGGAGCCCGUCUACCUGCCCGUAAACUGGAGUAAAGCCAGCUCCUUGUUCUGGAUCCAGAAUCCCCCAAGACGUGGCCAUUUGUCUCAAUGUCACCAAGCUUCAUCUUCCAACUUAUUCACGGGCCGGCUCCAACAGGUCCCAACAAUCUAGACACAGGCUGGUAAGCCAUUCCCGGCUGCUAGAGGCGCCAGGGCUGGGAGUUGGAAAAAUGGGUCACAGGGGCAGCCUUCAUUCCGCUAAGUGGGGCCGGCCCUUGGUGGAAUAAUAUUAAACAGAUGCAAUUCAGACCUAAGUUGUGAAGCCCACAGAUUGCUAGGCUAACUUGAAACAAGAUGGUUUUUGAGGAUAAGUGUUAUGGAAAAGCCAGUUUGUUUUUCAAACUUGAUGCUAAAAUAAACGUGAAGGCCUUCACAUGAA